GUCGCCUGCGCGUCUCUCGUUUUCGGACGGCUGCAGCAUCGCGGUGGGGAUCGAAAGCGGGGGCUUCUGGGACGCAGCUCUGGAGACGCGGCCUCGGACCAGCCAUUUCGGUGUAGAAGUGGCAGCACGGCAGGUCGGUGAGUCUCGGAGGCGGCAGCCGCUUCCUGAAGCCAUUCCCGCUGCUCUCCAGUGGGCAGGCAGAGGUUUGACCCACACGGAGUGAUAGCGGGAAGAAGACAGUGUGAACCGUGCGGGUGCGGGUCCUUAGAUGAGAAAAUUCGAAGUAGCGAUGAGAUGUGAGAAAUGGCGGUGUUCCUGACUGACCUGCCUUCUUGCAGCUUUUCUUCUUUUUCUCCGCAUUUGGCAUUUGUACACUUCAUUUUUCCCGCUUGAGGCUUAUCUCCAUCUCUUCUGCUGUGGACCGUGGCCAUCUCGUUACUUAACAGCUUCUGACUAACGCAGGGCAGUUUGUUCAGCGACUGCAACUCUGUGUUAGGGGAAACCUGGGGUGAGGUAGCCCGCCAUCUCCCCGUAGGUGAAUACCGCAAGCCUCCGAAUUUGGCGUGGUGGGCGACUCUCGUGGAAUGGGCAGCUAGACAUCACAACCCUACAUUUUUACCCUCCAUCUCUAGAUUGAAGUGUUGGGGUGUUGUUUUAUCAAGGAAGCUGAUUCAUCUGAAAACUACAUUAAGAUGAAGACCUUUGAAGGUUUCUGUGCUUUGCAUCUCGCUGCAAGUCAAGGACAUUGGAAAAUCGUACAGAUUCUUUUAGAAGCUGGGGCAGAUCCUAAUGCAACUACUUUAGAAGAAACGACACCAUUGUUUUUAGCUGUUGAAAAUGGACAGAUAGAUGUGUUAAGGCUGUUGCUUCAACACGGAGCAAAUGUUAAUGGAUCCCAUUCUAUGUGUGGAUGGAACUCCUUGCACCAGGCUUCUUUUCAGGAAAAUGCUGAGAUCAUAAAAUUGCUUCUUAGAAAAGGAGCAAACAAGGAAUGCCAGGAUGACUUUGGAAUCACACCUUUAUUUGUGGCUGCUCAGUAUGGCAAGCUAGAAAGCUUGAGCAUACUUAUUUCAUCGGGUGCAAAUGUCAAUUGUCAAGCCUUGGACAAAGCUACACCCUUGUUCAUUGCUGCUCAAGAGGGACACACAAAAUGUGUGGAGCUUUUGCUCUCCAGUGGGGCAGAUCCUGAUCUUUACUGUAAUGAGGACAGUUGGCAGUUACCUAUUCAUGCAGCUGCACAAAUGGGCCAUACAAAAAUCUUGGACUUGUUAAUACCACUUACUAACCGGGCCUGUGACACUGGGCUAAACAAAGUAAGCCCUGUUUACUCAGCAGUGUUUGGGGGACAUGAAGAUUGCCUAGAAAUAUUACUCCGGAAUGGCUACAGCCCAGACGCCCAGGCGUGCCUUGUUUUUGGAUUCAGUUCUCCUGUGUGCAUGGCUUUCCAAAAGGACUGUGAGUUCUUUGGAAUUGUGAACAUUCUUUUGAAAUAUGGAGCCCAGAUAAAUGAACUUCAUUUGGCAUACUGCCUGAAGUACGAGAAGUUUUCGAUAUUUCGCUACUUUUUGAGGAAAGGUUGCUCAUUGGGACCAUGGAACCAUAUAUAUGAAUUUGUAAAUCAUGCAAUUAAAGCACAAGCAAAAUAUAAGGAGUGGUUGCCACAUCUUCUGGUUGCUGGAUUUGACCCACUGAUUCUACUGUGCAAUUCUUGGAUUGACUCAGUCAGCAUUGACACCCUUAUCUUCACUUUGGAGUUUACUAAUUGGAAGACACUUGCACCAGCUGUUGAAAGGAUGCUCUCUGCUCGUGCCUCAAACGCUUGGAUUCUACAGCAACAUAUUGCCACUGUUCCAUCCCUGACCCAUCUUUGUCGUUUGGAAAUUCGGUCCAGUCUAAAAUCAGAACGUCUACGGUCUGACAGUUAUAUUAGUCAGCUGCCACUUCCCAGAAGCCUACAUAAUUAUUUGCUCUAUGAAGACGUUCUGAGGAUGUAUGAAGUUCCAGAACUGGCAGCUAUUCAAGAUGGAUAAAUCAGUGAAACUACUUAACACAGCUAAUUUUUUUCUCUGAAAAAUCAUCGAGACAAAAGAGCCACAGAGUACAAGUUUUUAUGAUUUUAUAGUCAAAAGAUGAUUAUUGAUUGUGAGAUAGGUUAGGUUUUGGGGGGCCAGUAGUUCAGUGAGAAUGUUUAUGUUUACAACUAGCCUUCCCAGUAAAAAAAAAAAAAAAAAAAAAAAAAAUUGUAAACAUCACUUAUAUUACUUUAUUGCAGCUUCAUCACCAGUACAUUAUAUGUUGUAAUAUUUAUUUACCUGAUCAUUUUGAUCAUUUUCUGCUUUAUUUUGCUAAUAAACUGUGAUGUUACUUCUAGUGCUAAACAUGGCAUAUUUCCACCUAUGAUUCGUGUUUACCUGGUAUUAGGAGCUCAGAAUGGAAUGCAUAAAGCUUCACUGGAAGUGUAUACAACUGUGGUGUAGAAUCUGUUAUUAUUAUCAUUAUUAUUUUAUUUAGACUUGACUAUCUCUUAUGUUUAUUAAAGAACAUGUUUUCCUA